GGGCGCCCGCGGCCUCCGCACCCGGACCUGAGGUGUUGGUCGACUCCGGGCAUCCACGGUCGGGAGGGAGGGCUGAGCUGUUCGAUCCUUUACUUUUCUUCCUCAAAGUCUACCUGCCAAUGCCCCUAAGAAGAAAACCAAGUAUGUGCGUGGAGAGUGGGGCGGCAGGCAACCCGAGUUCUUGAGCUCCGGAGCGACCCAAAGCAGCAACUGGGAACAGCCUCAGGAAAGGGAGGUCGGGUGGAGUGGGCUUUGGGGCAGGAGUCAUGGGGCCCGGGCCCCGGGGACGACCUGGCGCUCCCGGCCCUGCUGAACGCUGAGUUGCGCCUAGUCGGGUUUUCGAAGAGGCCCUUGCGCAGAGCGACCCACGCGCGCGGCAGCAUCUUCGAUUAGUCAGGACAUCCCAGUAACUGCUUGAACUGUAGGAGCCAUUCCGUAGUGCCAUCCCGAGCAACGCACUGCUGCAGCUUCCCUGAGCCUUUCCAGCAAGUUUGUUCAAGAUUGGCUGUCAAGAAUCAUGGACUGUUAUUAUAUGCCUUGUUUUCUGUCAAGACACCAUGAUUCCUGGUAACCGAAUGCUGAUGGUCGUUUUAUUAUGCCAAGUCCUGCUAGGAGGCGCGAGCCAUGCUAGUUUGAUACCUGAGACGGGGAAGAAAAAAGUCGCCGAGAUUCAGGGCCACGCGGGAGGACGCCGCUCAGGGCAGAGCCAUGAGCUCCUGCGGGACUUCGAGGCGACACUUCUGCAGAUGUUUGGGCUGCGCCGCCGCCCGCAGCCUAGCAAGAGUGCCGUCAUUCCGGACUACAUGCGGGAUCUUUACCGGCUUCAGUCUGGGGAGGAGGAGGAAGAGCAGAUCCACAGCACUGGUCUUGAGUAUCCUGAGCGCCCGGCCAGCCGGGCCAACACCGUGAGGAGCUUCCACCACGAAGAACAUCUGGAGAACAUCCCAGGGACCAGUGAAAACUCUGCUUUUCGUUUCCUCUUUAACCUCAGCAGCAUCCCUGAGAACGAGGUGAUCUCCUCUGCAGAGCUUCGGCUCUUCCGGGAGCAGGUGGACCAGGGCCCUGAUUGGGAAAGGGGCUUCCACCGUAUAAACAUUUAUGAGGUUAUGAAGCCCCCAGCAGAAGUGGUGCCUGGGCACCUCAUCACACGACUACUGGACACGAGACUGGUCCACCACAAUGUGACACGGUGGGAAACUUUUGAUGUGAGCCCUGCGGUCCUUCGCUGGACCCGGGAGAAGCAGCCAAACUAUGGGCUAGCCAUUGAGGUGACUCACCUCCAUCAGACUCGGACCCACCAGGGCCAGCAUGUCAGGAUUAGCCGAUCGUUACCUCAAGGGAGUGGGAAUUGGGCCCAGCUCCGGCCCCUCCUGGUCACCUUUGGCCAUGAUGGCCGGGGCCAUGCCUUGACCCGACGCCGGAGGGCCAAGCGUAGCCCUAAGCAUCACUCACAGCGGGCCAGGAAGAAGAAUAAGAACUGCCGGCGCCACUCGCUCUAUGUGGACUUCAGCGAUGUGGGCUGGAAUGACUGGAUUGUGGCCCCACCAGGCUACCAGGCCUUCUACUGCCAUGGGGACUGCCCCUUUCCACUGGCUGACCACCUCAACUCAACCAACCAUGCCAUUGUGCAGACCCUGGUCAAUUCUGUCAAUUCCAGUAUCCCCAAAGCCUGUUGUGUGCCCACUGAACUGAGUGCCAUCUCCAUGCUGUACCUGGAUGAGUAUGAUAAGGUGGUACUGAAAAAUUAUCAGGAGAUGGUAGUAGAGGGAUGUGGGUGCCGCUGAGAUCAGGCAGUCCUUGAGGAUAGACAGAUAUACACACCACACACACACACCACAUACACCACACACACACGUUCCCAUCCACUCACCCACACACUACACAGACUGCUUCCUUAUAGCUGGACUUUUAUUUAAAAAAAAAAAAAAAAAAGGAAAAAAUCCCUAAACAUUCACCUUGACCUUAUUUAUGACUUUACGUGCAAAUGUUUUGACCAUAUUGAUCAUAUAUUUUGACAAAAUAUAUUUAUAACUACGUAUUAAAAGAAAAAAAUAAAAUGAGUCAUUAUUUUAAAGGUAAA